CUUUUCUGAGCGCGUUUGCCUGUUGAGUGGUAGCCUUUCCCCUCAACCAGCAAUGGAGGAGCAGCCCCAGAUGCAAGACGCCGACGAGCCCGCGGACUCCGGAGGGGAAGGCCGGGCAGGCGGGCCACCGCAGGUCGCCGGCGCCCAGGCGGCGUGCAGCGAGGACCGCAUGACCCUGCUCCUCAGGCUGAGAGCACAGACAAAACAACAACUCUUAGAAUAUAAAUCAAUGGUUGAUGCAAGUGAAGAAAAAACUCCAGAACAAAUUAUGCAAGAAAAGCAAAUCGAAGCUAAAAUUGAAGACCUGGAAAAUGAAAUUGAAGAGGUAAAAGUUGCUUUUGAGAUAAAAAAGCUUGCAUUAGACAGGAUGAGACUUUCAACUGCACUUAAAAAAAACCUGGAGAAAAUUAGCAGACAGUCUAGUGUGCUCAUGGAUAACAUGAAACACCUAUUAGAGCUAAAUAAAUUAAUAAUGAAAUCACAGCAGGAAUCUUGGGAUUUAGAGGAAAAACUGCUUGAUAUUAGAAAGAAGAGAUUGCAAUUAAAACAAGCUUCAGAAAGUAAGCUUUUAGAAAUACAGACUGAAAAGAACAAACAGAAGAUUGAUUUGGACAGUAUGGAAAACUCAGAGAGGAUAAAGAUCAUACGACAAAACCUACAGAUGGAGAUAAAAAUUACUACUGUUAUUCAACAUGUGUUCCAGAACCUUAUUUUGGGGAGUAAAGUCAAUUGGGCAGAGGAUCCUGCCCUUAAGGAAAUUGUUCUGCAGCUUGAGAAGAAUGUUGACAUGAUGUAAUAAGAAUUCAUUUCUGACAUAUUUUACAUUUCUGGCAAUCUCAACUCUUAUUUGGAAUACUUCUGUGCAUUUGUCUGUCCACCGUAAUUUUAGAAAAGCAUAUCCAUAACGUUUACAGUUGUAGUACAGUUGUGGUUAGUUAUUUGUAGUGGGAUUGAAAGUAAUUUUUUUCUUUUUAUAUUUCUAUAUUUAGUUUGUUUUUUUGUUGUUGUUGUUUUUUGAGAUGGAGUCUCGCUUUGUUGCCCAGACUGGAGGGCAGUGGCGCGAUCUCGGCUCACUGCAACCUCUGCCUCCCGGGUUCAAGCAGUUCUGCCUCAGCCUCCCAAGUAGCUGUGACUAAAGGUGCACGCCGCCAUGCCCAGCUAAUUUUUUGUAUUUUAGUAGAGACGGGGUUUCACCGUGUUGCCCAGGCUGCUCUCAGAACUCCUGAGCUCAGGCAGUCCACCGCCUCGGCCUACCGAAGUGCUAGGAUUACAGACGUAAGCCACCGAGCCUGGUCUAGUUUGCAUUUUUUUUCUAUCAGUUUUAUAAGUUAAGAAAUAAAAGGAAUUAAUGUUA